AGAUCGGAGAGGGCACAGGGCCAGGGACUCUGGCCAGACAUAGGCCCAGGUCUGUGGCUGGCCAGCUGCAGCUGUGGGGCCUGGCAUGUGUCUCAACAUGGCCCUGGAGCUCUACAUGGACCUGCUGUCAGCACCCUGCCGUGCCGUCUACAUCUUCUCGAAGAAGCAUGACAUCCAGUUCAACUUUCAGUUUGUGGAUCUGCUGAAAGGUCACCACCACAGCAAAGAAUACAUUGACAUCAACCCCCUCAGGAAGCUUCCCAGCCUCAAAGAUGGGAAAUUUAUCUUAAGUGAAAGCAGACAAGAGUACAGAGACCUGGCAGGGCAGGUGGCCCUGGAGUGCAGCCUCCUCUUCCCUCCUCUUCCCAACCCUGGCCAGUUGCUGAUCCCAAAGAUAACAGGGGAGGAAGUUUCAGCUGAGAAGAUGGAGCAUGCAGUGGAAGAGGUGAAGAACAGCCUGCAGCUCUUUGAGGAGUAUUUUCUGCAGGAUAAGAUGUUCAUCACCGGGAACCAAAUCUCACUGGCUGACCUGGUGGCCGUGGUGGAGAUGAUGCAGGCCAGCAGCACAGCGAUGCCUUUGCCCAGGUGAACCCCCUGAGGAAGGUGCCGGGCCUUGAAGGAUGGGGACUUCACCUUGGCUGAGAGGUAACCGGUCCGUGGGCUGCUGCCGGGCCUUGUGGGGCCAGUCGGCUGUCUGUUCACUGUUGAUGGCUUGGAUCAUGGACUGUGGGCCCUGCACCAGCCCCAGGGUGAAGAAUGGGUGGAGGCAGGCAGUGGUGCCCAGUGUUGACAAGGGUUAUAGAAGUCCCCUCCUGCAUUGUACAAGUGAGGAAACUGAGGCUGGAGGAGGGGAGGGACUUGCACAAGGCCACAGGGCCCAGUCUGCUUCCGGGCCUCCUCACCGCCAGCCUUCCCCUCCGAAAAAAGGAGAGUGCUAAGUUUCGAGGAGCGGCUGUACCAGGCAUCUUAGUGCUACCAUUUUGCCCACAAAUCCUGUGGGGCAAGUGCUGUUUCCCUGGAGAGUCGAGGGACCACUCAGCGAGCUUCAGUGGCUAUUUGCUAAACAUCCACCAGGGCCAGACCCCAUUUAAGCCCUGGGGCUUGAGCAGUGAACGUGUCUACGUCCUUCUCCUCAUGGAUCUCACAUUCCAUUAAUAGAAGGGGGAGCUGACAGUAACCCAUGUAAACAUGGAACAUAUCGGAUGUUGAUGGAUGCCAUGGAAAAAAUAAACAGGGUAAGAUUGGGGGUGUGUGAGUAGGAUGUUGAGGGAAGACUCCCUGGAGGAAGUGGCAUCUGAGCAGAGAGCUGUAGGAAUGUGCAAGGCAUGAGGAGAAGGGUGUUCUGGCUGGAGGGAAGAGUGAGGGCGAAGGCUCCAGGUGGGACAAUGCAUGGGGUUCAGACUGGAGAGCAACGGGCCAGGGUGGGUGUAGUGAGCAGGAAGAG